CCACCCUUUCAGGAACCCUGUAUGGUUUUUAGUUUAAAUUAAAGGAGUCGUUAUCGUGGUGGGAAUAUGAAAUAAAGUAGAAGAAAAGGCCAUGAGCUAGUCUGCUGGUGCUUGCUGUUGGGGAAGGGAAGGUGAUGGUGUGUUGGACUCCAGGGGCCCUCAUGGCCCAGCCCACCCUCCCCAGAUUGAAAACCAGGACAGAUUUGUGCUCAGUGGAUUGGGUGGUGUUUUUAGUAUGGAGCAGAACAGAAUUCCUAGGACUGCGUGUGAUGAAAUGCAAGGUCAAAAGGAAAAGACAAAGCAUAUUUCAAAGAUGAGAAAUAUUUGUUUGGAUAUCUAUGACUGUCUGUUUAUACUGUAAGGGGCUUAAUCAGCAGCUCCAUCUUUUAGUUUUAGUUCUAAAGGAAAAGUAGCCUAAAGUCAGUAUAACUAAAGGGUGGAACGAGGUGGGACAAGGUCCGGAAUUGCUGCUCAGUGAUGUGUGUGUGCCUGCCGCUGGUGGAGCUGAGACUGCUCAUCUCAGAAGGAUGGGGAUGCUUGAUUUCCUGGCCAGGUUGUCCCAGCACAGUGGGGAUUGGCCCUGUUGUAUGACGAAGACAGCACAUGGUGGCAGAGAUAGAUACUAACCCAUGGACUUUCCAAGGGAGGGAAUAGGUCUUUGGAGGGUAUGCAAGACAAAGGUAGACACUGGAUAAAGAACCCGGUAGUGCCCAGGUAUUACCCCAUCUGGGCCAUUACUCCCACACUCAGGAACCAGACGUUGUGGGUGAGGACAUGCUGUCCCUCCUGCCAAGUAAUAACUUCCUUCCCAGCCAGGAUCCUGCCCCAAGUAGGAAUAUAGCUCUGCAUUUACAGCAGCUCCUGCUCAGACCUUGUCAAAACCACCCUGCAGCUUAGGAUUAAGGAGCAUGGUCACAGGAAGGUGGGGUUUCAGGGCAUCCCCUCAGGAACUGCCCAUCUCCCCAGAAUUCCAAAAUGAAGGUCCAUAUGCUUGUAGGUGUGCUGGUCAUGGUGGGCUUCACAGUAGGAAAGGUUCCUGUUCCCGACAUCCGGACGUGCCACUUCUGCCUCGUAGAAGACCCUUCUGUAGGAUGCAUUUCAGGCUCAGAGAAGUGUACCAUCAGCAGCUCAUCCCUGUGCAUGGUGAUCACCAUCUAUUAUGAUGUCAAGGUUCGCUUCAUCGUUCGAGGCUGUGGACAGUACAUUUCCUACCGCUGCCAAGAAAAACGCAACACCUACUUUGCAGAGUACUGGUAUCAGGCCCAGUGCUGUCAGUACGAUUAUUGCAACUCCUGGUCAAGCCCCCAACUCCAGAGCUCUCUGCCGGAGCCCCAUGACAGGCCCCUGGCCCUGCCUCUGUCUGACUCCCAGAUUCAGUGGUUCUACCAGGCCCUGAACCUCUCCCUGCCCCUCCCCAAUUUCCAUGCUGGGACGGAGCCUGAUGGCCUGGACCCCAUGGUCACACUGUCCCUGAACCUGGGCUUGUCUUUUGCUGAGCUGCGCCGCAUGUACUUGUUCCUCAAUAGUUCAGGACUUUUGGUUCUUCCCCAGGCUGGACUCUUGACACCUCACCCUUCCUGAAUUCCACAGUGCAAAUAUCUUUCUGUAACACCCUCAGCAUCCUGCACUGCCCUCUCUGAAAACACCCACAUUCUUUGGUCACUGUGAUUUCUUAGGCCUCCGUCUGUUGUACCACUAGCAUCUAUAUGACUUUUGUGUAAUUUUCUCUCUUGAACUCUGGUGCUGUUUUUUUGUUUGUUUGAGACAAAGUCUCGCUCUGUCACCCAGGGUGGAGUGCAGUGGCAUGAUCUCUGCUCACUACAACCUCCACCUCCCGGGUUCCAGCGAUUCUCCUGCCUCAGCCUCCCGAGUAGCUGGGACUACAGGCGUGCACCACCACGCCUGGCUAAUUUUUUGUAUUUUUAGUAGAGACGGGGUUUCACCAUGUUGGUCAGGCUGGUCUCGAACUCCUGACCUCGUAAUCUGCCCUCCUCGACCUCCCAAAGUGCCGGGAUUACAGGUGUGAGCCACUGUGCCUGUCUGAGCUCUGGUGCUGUUCUUCCCCCUAGAAAAGAAUCUCUAGUGUGGAUUCUGCCCAGACAGGCUGACCUGAGAAAGGCACAGUGGUUCCUCCAUUCCUUCCCCAUCAUCUGAGUGUUCCAGUAUCCCCCAUCCCUCUCAAUCCAGUCACCUGCCUAUUGACAUCUAGCUCUGUUUCCCCUGUCUUGUCCAUGUCUCUAAGACCCAGUACCAGACUGAACUAGCAGCAAGAAGGACGAGGAGGCCGGGCAUGGUGGCUCACGCCGGUAAUCCCAGCACUUUGGGAGGCCGAGGUGGGCGGAUCACUUGAGAUUGGGAGUUUGAGACCAGCCUGGCCAACAUGGUAAAACCCGCUCUCUAUUAAAAAUAGAAAAAUCAGCUGGGUGUGGUGGCACACCUCUGUAAUCCCAGCUACUCAGGAGGCUGAGACAGGAGAAUCACUUGAACCCGGGAGGCAGAGGUUGCAGUGAGCCGAGAUCGCGCCACUGCACUCCAGCCUGGGUGACACAGUGAGACUCCGUCUCCAAAAAAAAGGAUGAGGAAUAGAAUUCUGUGCAGAUGUCCUGACUUGGCAAUUUUGUGUCCCUGCCUCACUGUCUCCACCAACCCCCGCCUGUCCUAGUGUUGUUCUGCCUCCUGUCCUCUCUUGCUCUCUUGUCAGUCUCUGGCUUCCUCGGCCCCAUUUCACUUCACUGAGUCCUGACACCCAUCUCCCUAGGGGCCUGUGAGAGGAGAGGGAAGGGUCUGUUCUGCUCAGCUCCAUGUCCCCCAUUUUCCUCCACAAUAAACUGGGACUGGGCUAAAA